GGACCGGAAGUGGAAGUGGUCCCCGAAGGCUAUUUCGCCGCUGGCGUCAGGACUAUUUUCACGUUUUAAUGCCGAGAGGUCUCUGUGACGAUUUUGGUUCUUGGGUGUCUCUGGGGAGUCCCUGGGCCAGACCUUCCUCCAGACUCCAGCCCACCUCUUCGGAGCAGCUCUGCUGAGUUCACAGAUGACCACUAAACUUCAGGCACCCUAGACAAAAAGGGUUGAGAUCCAGUGUGGCCAUGCCAGCUAGUUGGACCUCACCCCAGAAAUCCUCAGCCCUGGCUCCAGAGGAUCAUGGCAGCUCCUAUGAGGGAUCAGUGUCCUUCAGGGAUGUGGCUAUCGAUUUCAGCAGAGAGGAAUGGCGGCACCUGGACCUUUCUCAGAGAAACCUGUACCGGGAUGUGAUGCUGGAGACCUACAGCCACCUGCUCUCAGUAGGGUAUCAAGUUCCUAAACCAGAGGUGGUCAUGUUGGAGCAAGGAAAGGAACCAUGGGCACUGCAGGGUGAGAGGCCACGUCACAGCUGCCCAGGAGAGAAAUUAUGGGACCAUAAUCAACAUAGAAAAAUCAUCGGUUAUAAACCAGCUUCCUCUCAAGAUCAAAAAAUUUAUUCUGGGGAAAAAUCCUAUGAGUGUGCUGAAUUUGGAAAGAGCUUCACCUGGAAGUCACAGUUCAAGGUACAUCUGAAAGUUCCUACAGGAGAAAAACUCUAUGUAUGUAUUGAAUGUGGGAGGGCUUUUGUACAGAAGCCAGAAUUCAUCACACAUCAGAAAACCCAUAUGAGAGAGAAGCCCUAUAAGUGCAAUGAAUGUGGAAAAUCCUUUUUUCAAGUAUCGUCUCUUUUCAGGCAUCACAGAAUUCAUACCGGAGAAAAACUAUAUGAAUGUAGUGAAUGUGGGAAAGGUUUCCCUUAUAACUCAGAUCUCAGUAUACAUGAGAAAAUUCAUACUGGAGAGAGACACCAUGAAUGCACUGACUGUGGCAAAGCGUUCACACAAAAGUCCACACUCAAGAUUCAUCAGAAAAUCCAUACAGGCGAGAGAUCCUACAUCUGUAUUGAAUGCGGGCAGGCCUUCAUCCAGAAAACACAAUUGAUUGCACACCGAAGAAUUCAUAGUGGAGAAAAACCAUAUGAAUGCAAUAACUGUGGCAAAUCCUUCAUUUCCAAGUCACAACUUCAGGUACAUCAACGUGUUCACACAAGAGUGAAGCCCUAUAUAUGUACCGAAUAUGGGAAGGUCUUCAGCAAUAAUUCCAACCUCAUUACACAUGAGAAGAUUCAAAGUAGAGAGAAAUCUUCCAUAUGUACUGAGUGUGGGAAGGCCUUUACCUACAGGUCAGAGUUGAUUAUUCAUCAGAGAAUUCACACUGGAGAGAAACCUUAUGAAUGCAGUGACUGUGGGAGAGCCUUCACUCAGAAGUCAGCACUCACAGUGCAUCAGAGAAUUCAUACAGGAGAAAAAUCGUAUAUAUGCAUGAAAUGUGGACUGGCCUUCAUCCGGAAGGCACACUUGAUUACACAUCAAAUAAUUCAUACUGGAGAGAAACCUUAUAAAUGUGGUCACUGUGGGAAAUUGUUUACUUCCAAGUCACAACUCCAUGUUCAUAAACGAAUUCACACAGGAGAAAAGCCCUAUGUAUGCAAUAAAUGUGGGAAGGCAUUCACCAACCGGUCAAAUCUCAUUACACAUCAGAAAACUCAUACAGGAGAGAAAUCUUAUAUAUGUUCCAAAUGUGGAAAGGCCUUCACCCAGAGGUCAGACUUGAUUACACAUCAGAGAAUCCAUACUGGGGAGAAGCCUUAUGAAUGCAAUACUUGUGGAAAAGCCUUUACUCAGAAGUCAAAUCUUAAUAUACAUCAGAAAAUUCACACUGGAGAGAGACAGUAUGAAUGCCACGAAUGUGGGAAAGCCUUCAACCAGAAAUCAAUACUCAUUGUUCAUCAGAAAAUUCAUACAGGAGAGAAACCCUAUGUAUGCACUGAGUGUGGAAGAGCUUUCAUCCGCAAGUCAAACUUUAUUACUCAUCAAAGAAUUCAUACUGGAGAGAAGCCUUAUGAAUGCAGUGACUGUGGGAAGUCCUUUACCUCCAAGUCUCAGCUCCUGGUGCAUCAGCCAGUUCACACAGGAGAGAAACCCUAUGUGUGUGCCGAGUGUGGGAAAGCCUUUAGUGGCAGGUCAAAUCUCAGUAAGCACCAGAAAACUCAUACCGGAGAAAAGCCCUACAUUUGUUCUGAAUGUGGGAAGACCUUUCGACAGAAGUCAGAGUUGAUUACACAUCACAGAAUUCAUACUGGAGAGAAACCUUAUGAGUGCAGUGACUGUGGGAAGUCUUUCACUAAAAAAUCACAGCUCCAAGUGCAUCAGCGAAUUCACACUGGAGAGAAGCCUUACGUGUGUGCUGAGUGUGGGAAGGCCUUUAGCAACAGGUCCAAUUUGAAUAAACAUCAGACAACACACACUGGAGACAAACCCUACAAGUGUGGCAUCUGUGGGAAAGGCUUCGUUCAGAAAUCAGUGUUCAGUGUUCAUCAGAGCAGCCACGCUUGAGAGAAACAGUGUGAGAAAACCCCCCUGAGGGUUGGGUCUGAUUGUACACUGUUGCACGCAUGCAGCAGAAAAAUAUGUAUAUUAUUGUAAAUAGAAAUGACCACAUCAGAAUGUCACACAUGGCUGUUCUGGAGAGGGCCUCUGAGAAGGCACUGAAUGAGGCGAGGGACCCUUCCUACAUUGUCACCAUCCCCAGUAAACCUUGGGUCAUUAUUCAUACUGACAAGGAACCGAGUCAAUUUGGUGAAUAGGAAAAGCCUUCUCAUGAAAACUACAAUAGAAUACUGUUACCAAAUUCUUCAUAAGAAAGAUCAUAUUAUGGGAAUGAUAAUCCUGUUUACUGUGGAUUAGGUAUAGUGCCAACAGUUUGAAUGGUAAGACAACAUAAUAUAUAUGAUAGUGAUGAAUCCUUCUGUGAGUUGUUUGUUCCAGAACACACUGUCUAGUAGAAUUGUGGGUAUUUUCUUCUUUUGAAUCGAACACAGUUGUGCAUAUCCAAUUCCCCAUUGAGUAUUUCUAUCAAGCAAGAGAUACUGCAAUAAGACAAACUCCCUGUGUAUUCAGACACAGACCUCAGAGCGUAUGUUGAGUCCCCAUUGUCAUAGAAAAAGACUUACAGUCCCCUUCAUUAUCUGCCAGGACUCUCUCUGAGCCCCACAGGUUCUCAGCACAUUGUGUUUGACACCCAGCACAGUGUUUUUUCUUUUUCUUUCUUUCUUUCUCUUUCUUUCUUUCUUUCUUUCUUUCUUUCUUUCUUUCUUUCUUUCUUUCUUUCUUUCUUUCCUUCUUUCUUUCUUUUUCUUUCUUUCUCUUUCUUUCUUUCUUUCUUUCUUUCUUUCUUUCUUUCUUUCUUUCUUUCUUUCUUUCUUUUUUUGAGACAGAGUCUUGCUCUGUCGGGCAAGCUAGAGUGCAGUGGCGCUAUCUUGGCUCACUGCAACCUCCGUCUCCCGGGCUCAAGCAAUUCUCCUGCCUCAGCCUCCUGAGUAGCUGGGAUUGCGUGUGCCACCACGCCCAGCUAAUUUUUGUAUGUUUAGUAGAAACGGGGGUUUCACCAUGCUGGCCAGGCUGGUCUCGAACUCCUGACCUCAUGAUCCGCCCGCCUCGGCCUCCCAAAGUCCUGGGAUUACGGACGUGAGCCACUGCGCCCGGCCCAGCACAGUGUUUUGUACACUCCCACCACCCUCAAGAAAGCCUUUGAGGUUAGGAUUUUCAGGUCAUCUGGGAGAACUUAAAUUCUUCCUUCUGCUAUUACAAUUCUUCUCACUCAGUUGCCUGCCUCUUUUUUUUUUUUAAUUUACUUGUGACUGAGUUGAAGCCCAGCAUUUUACUUUCCUUAAUGAUCUGACUUUCAUAAGUUGAUAAGUCAUGAAAUCAUUAUCUUACAUUAUAUGAGAUAUGAGAUAAAUCAUAAAUCAUAUGAAAUUGAUAACUCAUAUGAAAACCAACCCCACCAUAUGUUCACUGUCUACUUGUGUCCAUCUUCGUCCCACGCACCCCACAAGGACCUUCCCCGCCAUGUGCCUCAAACAUCAGUUCCUGACUCAGGGCCUUUGUAUUUGCAGUGCCCGUUGCAAAGAGCACAAUUCUUUAUUUUAUCUGUGGCUUGUCCGUCAUGUCUUUUUUUCCAUGACACCUCCACACAGGCCUUCCCUGCCUGCCUGGUUUAAAAUUCCAGCCCCUUACCCUUCCUCCUUUAUUCUUCUCCCUAGCAAUUUCCACCAUGCUGCCUGGUGUAUUUUCCUCAUUUCUCUGUGGCUUCUACACUAGAAAAUAUUUCCCUUUUGUUCACCACUAUGAGUCUAGACCCAUGACUGCCAUACAGCAGGCAUUCCAUAAAUGCACCUGUGGAGAGUUGACCCAUGCUUGUUGCGUGACUUCUGUCUGAUUUUUUUCUGUGUUGCAGCAUAAGAAGCGCUAAUAGGGAGAACCAACUUGGCUAAAACACACCAGGCUUUUUCACCUCUAGUCUGUACCUGGGCUGUAUCCCUUCUCAACCCUAAAGCUAAAAAGUCAUUGUGAACCUUUUGGUCUGAUGCUAAAGAAGGGAAAACAGGUACAGGAAAUCCCAUGUGGAUGCUUGCUUCCAGGAUUUCCUGCCAUGAUUCCAGAAUCCCACAGCUCCAACAUGAUUGCAAAAGACUCCCUGCUCAUUUUUCCUCAGCAUGCACAGCGCUGUCCUGUCUCAGUUGCAACUCGACAGAGCCGCAUUUACUCCAGAACCCAAUCCACACACCUGCUCAUCCUGCCCCGAGAGGAGUGCCUGAAGCCAAUAGCAGGGAACUAGAGCAGACUUGGGUGGAUCUUCAUUGGAUAUUAGGUAUCUUGCCCUAGAUAGGCAGCAGUGGCCUUACAGAUGCUGACAGAUGAUCUGAUUAGAUGCACAGUUGCUGGGUGGCGUCUGGGGCCAGUCUAUUGGCAGUUCUGGGAGUGGGAACUAUUUGGGCUCUGCAAAGAUGGUUUCACCUUUAAGAAGGGCAGUAUGGGGAGGUGAAGAUGGGGCCCAAAGGAUAGAACAUAGUCAAAGAAGCAGGGCCACAAUGCCCCUUUAAUUCCCAAGCCCUAGUUGGGCAGUGCUUGGUGACACAUCCCAUUACCUCACCUUAGAUCAAUGUCUACUGAGCCAUCAUUAGCUCUGCUUCCUCACUUCUUCACAGUAUCUGAUGGCCCAUCACAUGCUGCUCAACAUCUUAGACCAAUGUCUGCUCACCCAUUACCUCCCUUCACCUCAUCCAGCACUGUAUCUGAAGCUUCACUAUUCUUCCUUCAGUUUUGGAUAUUUUGUGAUACAACAUUAUCCCCAACUUAGGACAAUGUCAGCUGACUCUCAGGAGGGUGCCUGGAGAUCACCUCUUCCUUCCUAACAUACCCUAGAACAAGGUCUGGUCCCCUUCAUUAUUCCCAUUUUACCUUACUCCUAAGUGUAUCACUCCUCAUGAAUUCCAGGAAAUAUGGAGGAAAACACAUUUCACUGUACAUGACUUUCAAUAAUUUCUCCUUUAUAUUUAUUGUAACGUGAUAUUUUAGUGCUGACAUAUAUAUGUAUAUGUAUGCCCAUUUAUAUAAAAGACUAGUUUUUAGAGAAAUUUUAGGUUCACAGCAAAAUGGGGCAGAAGGUACAGAGAUUUCCCAUAUAUCCCCUACCCUCACAUAUACACAGCCUCCCCCAUCAUCAACAUCCCCCUUCAGAGUGGUACAUUUGUUACAAUUGAUGAAACUACAUUGACACUAUCGGCCAAAGUCCAUGGUUUAAUUAGGGUUCAGUCUUGAUGUGCAUUCUGUGGGUUGAGACAAAUGAAUAAUGACAUGUAUGCAUUAUUACAGAAGGAUAAAGAGCCGUUUCACUGUCCCAAUAAUCCUCUGUGUUUCGCCUACUCCUCUAAACUCCUGGCUAUUUUCUUUUGUCUCCAUAAUUUUGCCUCUGAACCAUAAAGUAUGCAGCCUUUUCAGAUUGAUUUGUUUCACUUAGUAAUGUGGAUUUAAGUUUCUUCCAUGUCUUUUCGUAGCUUGCUAGCUCUUUUUUUUUUUUUUUUCUCAUUGAAUAAUAUGCUAUUGUCUGGAAGUACCAUGACUUAUUUAUCCAUUCACCUACUGAAGGACACCUUAAUUGCUUCCAAGUUUUGUUGAUUAUGAAUAAAGAUGCUAUAAACA